GCUCCUUCGCUCCUGCUUUCCCGGCUCGGUGGGGUCCCUUCGCGGCCACCCGGGGAGACGUCUUAGACAGUCGUGGUUCCUGUGAUCUGUGUCCUCUUUGCAGAAGUUCUGUGUCCAUCUCAUGUGCUGCGUGUGUCUGUAAAGCCUCAUUCCGUGCUGUCUGGCAGGAAGCUCCAUCUCAUCUCAUCAUCUCACGGCCCUGGCACUGCCUCAGCAUGGCCAUCUCAUCACGCCUCGCCCUGUGGGAGCAGAAGAUUCGGGAAGAGGACAAGAGCCCUCCACCAUCCUCGCCCCCUCCUCUUUUCUCUGUCAUCCCAGGGGGCUUCAUUAAGCAACUGGUCCGGGGGACUGAAAAAGAGGCCAAGGAAGCGAGACAGAGGAAGCAGUUAGCUGUCGCCUCUCCAGAACGAGAGGUGGAGACUGAGGCCAAAAGAGGUCAAGUGAUUUUCCCAAGGUCAUCAGACCAGAUAGAGGCAGAGCGAGGGGGAGAGCCUGUGUGUUCUCUGCUCUCACAAGAUGCCUGGAAAAGGACCAGUCUGAUCCCAGAAAUUUCCAUCAGCCAACCCAACAGCAAGUCCAGCAGUGGCACCAGAUCUGGAAGCCAGCAGAUCUCUCAGGACGACCAGUCAAGCUCUCCUGGGAGCUCAGACAUUCUGGGCAAGGAGAGCGAGGGGUCCCGCAGCCCCGACCCUGAGCAGAUGACAAGCAUCAAUGGUGAGAAGGCCCAGGAGCUGGGCUCCAGUGCGACACCAACCAAAAAGACUGUCCCCUUCAAGAGGGGCGUGAGGAGGGGUGAUGUGUUGUUGAUGGUGGCCAAGCUGGACCCGGACUCAGCCAAGCCAGAGAAGACUCAUCCCCAUGACGCCCCCCCUUGCAAGACCUCUCCCCCCGCCACAGAUACUGGAAAGGAAAAGAAAGGGGAGACCUCUAGGACUCCUUGUGGCUCCCAGGCCAGCACCGAGAUCUUGGCCCCGAAAGCUGAGAAGACCCGGACUGGGGGUCUUGGGGACCCAGGCCAAGGAACUGUGGCACUGAAAAAAGGCGAGGAGGGUCAAAGCAUAGUGGGGAAGGGGCUUGGGACCCCCAAGACCACAGAGCUGAAAGAGGCUGAGCCCCAGGGCAAAGACAGGCAGGGGACCAGGCCCCAAGCCCAAGGGCCCGGCGAGGGGGUGCGACCAGGGAAAGCAGAGAAGGAGGGAGCAGAGCCCACAAACACGGUGGAAAAGGGGAAUGUCUCUAAGGACGUAGGGAGUGAAGGGAAGCACGUAAGGCCCCAAAUCCCUGGGAGAAAGUGGGGAGGUUUCCUGGGAAGAAGGAGUAAGUGGGACGGUCCCCAGAAUAAGAAGGACAAAGAAGGGGUGCUCUUAAGUAAGGCAGAGAAGACAGGUGAGCCUCAGACCCAGAUGGAGAAGACAAGCCAAGUGCAGGGCGAGUUGGGGGACGAUCUGAGAAUGGGGGAGAAAGCAGGUGAGCUUCGGAGCACGACUGGGAAGGCAGGUGAGUCCUGGGAUAAGAAGGAAAAGAUGGGGCAACCCCAGGGUAAGUCCGGGAACGCAGGUGAAGCUCGGAGUCAGACAGAGAAGGGCUGUGAAGCCCCAAAGGAGGUGAGCACAAUGGUGGAGUCGCCAGCAGCUCCUGGGAAGGGAGGCUGGCCAGGAAGCCGUGGGCAGGAAGCAGAGGAGCCCUGCUCAAGAGCAGGUGAUGGGGCUGGUGCCCUGGAGACAGAGCUGGAAGGACCCAGCCAGCCUGCUCUGGAGAAGGAUGCAGAAAGGCCUCGGAUACGGAAGGAGAACCAAGACGGGCCAGCCCCGCAGGAGGAGGGCAAAGGAGGCCAGAGCAGAGACUCAGACCAGGCUCCUGAGGACAGAUGGUAUGAGGCAGAGAAAGUCUGGCUGGCUCAGAAGGAUGGAUUUACUCUUGCUACGGUGCUAAAGCCAGAUGAGGGAACAGCAGACCUGCCAGCAGGAAGGGUGAGACUUUGGAUUGAUGCUGACAAAACCAUCACUGAGGUGGAUGAGGAGCAUGUCCAUCGGGCCAACCCUCCUGAGCUGGACCAGGUCGAGGACCUGGCCUCUCUCAUCAGUGUCAACGAAUCCAGUGUCCUGAACACGCUUCUGCAGCGCUACAAAGCUCAGCUGCUGCACACCUGCACAGGGCCUGAUCUGAUUGUCCUCCAGCCCCGGGGGCCCUCGGUGCCUUCUGCAGGGAAGGUGCCCAAGGGCCGCCGGGAUGGCCUGCCUGCCCACAUUGGCUCCAUGGCACAGCGGGCAUACUGGGCGCUGCUGAACCAGCGGAGAGACCAGAGCAUUGUGGCCCUGGGCUGGAGUGGCGCUGGGAAGACCACCUGCUGUGAGCAGGUCCUGGAACACCUGGUGGGGAUGGCAGGCAGUGUGGAUGGCAGGGUCUCAGUGGAGAAGAUCCGAGCCACCUUCACUGUCCUCCGGGCCUUCGGCUCUGUGUCCAUGGCCCACAGCCGCAGUGCCACCCGGUUCUCCAUGGUGAUGUCGCUGGACUUCAACGCUACAGGCCGCAUCACAGCUGCUCAGCUCCAGACAAUGCUUUUGGAGAAGAGCCGCGUGGCACGGCAGCCGGAAGGGGAAAGUAACUUCCUGGUUUUCUCCCAGAUGCUGGCUGGAUUGGACUUGGAUCUCAGGACGGAGCUGAACCUGCACCAGAUGGCAGAUAGCAGCUCCUUUGGCAUGGGCGUGUGGUCCAAGCCUGAAGAUAAACAGAAGGCGGCAGCUGCCUUUGCCCAGCUCCAGGGUGCCAUGGAGAUGCUCGGCAUCUCAGAGAGCGAGCAGCGGGCUGUUUGGCGGGUCCUGGCAGCCAUCUACCACCUGGGUGCGGCGGGGGCCUGCAAAGUGGGUCGGAAGCAGUUCAUGAGGUUUGAGUGGGCAAACUACGCAGCUGAGGCCCUGGGCUGCGAGUAUGAGGAGCUGAACACGGCCACCUUCAAGCACCACCUUCGACAGAUCAUCCAGCAAAUGACGUUUGGGCCAAGCCGAUGGGGCCUCGAGGAUGAGGAAACCAGCUCAGGGCUCAAGAUGACAGGAGUGGACUGUGUGGAGGGGAUGGCCUCGGGCCUGUACCAGGAACUCUUUGCGGCUGUGGUCUCACUCAUCAACAGAUCCUUUUCCUCCCACCAUCUCUCCAUGGCCUCCAUCAUGGUGGUGGACUCUCCAGGCUUCCAGAACCCCCGGCACCAGGGCAAGGACCGGGCGGCCACCUUUGAGGAGCUGUGCCACAACUACGCCCAUGAGCGCCUGCAGCUGCUGUUCUACCAGCGGACCUUUGUCUCCACGCUACAGCGAUAUCAAGAGGAAGGUGUUCCUGUGCAGUUUGACCUCCCGGACCCCUCCCCAGGGACCACCGUGGCUGUUGUGGAUCAAAAUCCCUCUCAGCAGGUCCGCUUACCAGCUGGAGGAGGUGCCCAGGAUGCCAGAGGCCUUUUCUGGGUCUUAGAUGAGGAAGUCCAUGUAGAGGGCUCCAGUGACAGUGUGGUGCUCGAGCGUCUGUGUGCUGCUUUCGAGAAGAAAGGAGCUGGGACUGAAGGGUCCUCUGCCCUGCGGACCUGUGAGCAGCCCCUCCAGUGUGAGAUUUUCCACCAGUUGGGAUGGGACCCUGUGCGGUACGACCUCACGGGCUGGCUCCACAGAGCCAAGCCCAACCUCUCGGCCCUGGAUGCACCCCAGGUCCUGCACCAGUCAAAAAGAGAGGAGCUGCGGAGUCUAUUCCAGGCCCGGGCCAAGCUGCCUCCUGUGUGCCGGGCUGUGGCAGGCCUGGAGGGCACCUCCCAGCAGGCCCUGCAGAGGAGCCGCAUGGUGAGGAGGACCUUUGCCAGCAGCCUUGCCGCGGUGAGGAGGAAAGCCCCGUGCUCCCAGAUCAAGCUGCAGAUGGAUGCGCUGACCAGCAUGAUCAAAAGGUCCCGGCUGCACUUUAUCCACUGCCUGGUACCAAACCCUGUGGUGGAAAGCAGGAGUGGGCAGGAAUCUCCACCACCACCGCAGCCUGGUAGAGACAAGCCUGGGGCAGGUGGACCUCUGGCCCUGGAUAUCCCAGCACUGAGGGUCCAGCUUGCUGGGUUCCACAUCCUGGAGGCUCUGCGUCUGCAUAGGACAGGCUAUGCUGACCACAUGGGGCUCACUCGCUUCCGCCGGCAAUUCCAGGUGCUGGACGCUCCACUCCUGAAGAAGCUCAUGUCGACCUCCGAGGGAAUAGAUGAAAGGAAGGCCGUGGAGGAGCUCCUGGAGACCCUGGAUCUGGAAAAGAAGGCGGUGGCUGUGGGGCACAGCCAAGUUUUUCUCAAGGCAGGUGUGAUCUCCAGGCUUGAGAAGCAGCGAGAGAAGCUGGUAUCUCAGAGCAUCGUUCUCUUCCAGGCGGCUUGCAAGGGCUUUCUGUCUCGCCAGGAAUUCAAGAAGCUGAAGAUUCGCCGACUGGCUGCACAGUGCAUCCAGAAGAAUGUGGCUGUGUUCCUCGCAGUCAAGGACUGGCCAUGGUGGCAGCUGCUUGGUUCCCUCCAGCCUCUACUUAGUGCCACCAUUGGAACUGAGCAGCUCCGAGCCAAGGAGGAGGAGCUUACAACGCUAAGACGGAAGCUAGAAAAAUCAGAGAAGUUGCGGAAUGAACUCCGGCAGAACACAGAUCUGCUAGAAAGCAAGAUUGCUGACUUGACCUCUGACCUUGCCGAUGAGCGCUUCAAAGGUGAUGUGGCCUGCCAGGUGCUGGAGAGUGAGCGGGCAGAGCGGCUACAGGCCUUCCGGGAGGUCCAGGAGCUCAAGAGCAAGCAUGAACAAGUCCAGAAAAAACUGGGAGAUGUGAAUAAACAGUUGGAAGAAGCCCAGCAGAAAAUUCAGUUGAAUGACUUGGAAAGGAAUCCCACUGGAGGAGCAGACGAGUGGCAGAUGCGCUUCGACUGUGCUCAGAUGGAGAACGAGUUCCUCAGAAAGCGUCUGCAGCAAUGCGAGGAGAGGCUGGACUCGGAGCUGACAGCCAGGAAAGAGCUGGAGCAAAAGCUUGGGGAGUUGCAAAGUGCUUAUGACGGGGCCAAGAAGAUGGCUCACCAACUGAAGAGGAAGUGCCACCAUCUUACCUGUGACCUUGAGGAUACCUGCGUCCUGCUAGAGAACCAACAAAGUCGAAACCAUGAGCUGGAGAAGAAGCAGAAGAAGUUUGACCUGCAGCUGGCCCAGGCCCUAGGUGAGUCAGUGUUUGAGAAGGGUCUCCGUGAGAAAGUGACCCAGGAGAACACCAGUGUCCGGUGGGAGCUAGGCCAGCUUCAGCAGCAGCUGAAGCAAAAGGAGCAGGAAGCCUCACAGCUGAAGCAGCAGGUGGAGAUGCUACAGGACCAUAAACGGGAGCUGCUGGGGUCACCCUCUCUGGGGGAAAAUUGCGUUGCUGGCUUGAAGGAGAGGCUCUGGAAGUUGGAAUCCAGCGCCCUUGAGCAACAGAAAAUCCAGAGCCAGCAGGAAAACACCAUCAAGCAGCUGGAGCAGCUCCGCCAGCGGUUUGAGCUGGAGAUCGAGCGGAUGAAGCAGAUGCACCAGAAGGACCGUGAGGACCAGGAGGAGGAACUGGAGGAUGUCCGUCAGUCCUGCCAGAAGCGGCUUCAUCAGCUGGAAAUGCAGCUGGAGCAAGAGUAUGAAGAGAAGCAGAUGGUCCUCCAUGAGAAGCAAGAUUUGGAAGGCUUGAUCGGAACCCUCUGUGACCAGAUUGGCCAUCGGGACUUUGAUGUGGAGAAGCGACUUCGGAGAGACCUCAGGAGGACACAUGCACUGUUGUCAGACGUGCAGCUCCUUCUGGGCACCAUGGAGGAUGGCAAGACAUCAGUCAGCAAGGAGGAGCUGGAGAAAGUGCACAGCCAGCUGGAGCAGAGUGAAGCCAAGUGUGAGGAGGCCUUGAAGACGCAGAAGGUGCUCACAGCGGACCUGGAGAGCAUGCACAGCGAGCUGGAGAACAUGACGCGGAACAAGAGCCUGGUGGAUGAGCAGCUGUACAGGCUGCAGUUUGAGAAGGCGGACCUCCUGAAGCGCAUCGAUGAGGACCAGGAUGACCUGAAUGAGCUGAUGCAGAAGCACAAGGACCUCAUUGCUCAGUCUGCUGCUGACAUUGGGCAGAUCCAAGAACUGCAGCUGCAGCUGGAGGAAGCCAAGAAGGAGAAGCACAAGCUACAAGAACAACUGCAGGUGGCUCAGAUGCGCAUCGAGUACCUGGAACAGUCCACCGUGGAUCGAGCCAUCGUCAGCAGGCAGGAGGCGGUCAUCUGUGACCUAGAGAACAAGACAGAGUUCCAGAAGGUGCAGAUUAAGAGAUUUGAGGUCCUGGUGAUCCGGCUUCGGGACAGCCUGAUCAAGAUGGGGGAGGAGCUUUCACAGGCGGCCACCUCCGAGUCCCAGCAGCGGGAGAGCAGCCAGUACUACCAGCGGCGCCUGGAAGAGCUGAAGGCCGACAUGGAAGAGCUGGUGCAGCGGGAGGCAGAGGCCAGCCGGCGGUGCAUGGAGCUGGAGAAGUACGUGGAGGAACUUGCAGCAGUGAGGCAAACCCUCCAGACAGACCUGGAGACAUCCAUUCGGCGGAUUGCCGACCUGCAGGCUGCCUUGGAAGAAGUGGCAUCCAGUGACAGUGAUACUGAGAGUGUCCAGACGGCAGUGGAUUGUGGCAGCAGCGGCCGAAAAGAGAUGGAUAACGUCUCCAUCCUCAGCUCCCAGCCAGAGGGCAGCCUGCAGUCCUGGUUGAGCUGUACUCUGUCCCUGGCCACAGAUACUAUGAGGACUCCUUCUCGACAGUCAGCCACCAGCAGCCGCAUCCUCAGCCCCAGGAUAAACGAAGAGGCUGGGGACACUGAGAGGACCCAGUCGGCAUUGGCACUGAGCAGAGCCCGGUCCACCAAUGUCCACAGCAAGACCUCAGGAGACAAGCCUGUUUCUCCCCACUUUGUCCGCCGGCAAAAGUACUGUCAUUUUGGGGACGGCGAAGUGCUUGCCGUCCAGAGAAAGUCCACAGAGAGAUUAGAACCUGCUUCCUCUCCCCUGGCUUCUCGGAGUACAAAUACAUCCCCGCUGUCGAGGGAAAAGCUGCCCAGUCCUUCAGCGGCCCUCUCGGAGUUCGUGGAAGGGCUCCGGAGGAAGAGAGCCCAGAGAGGCCAGGGGUCCACGCUGGGCCUAGAGGACUGGCCCACUCUCCCCAUUUACCAGACGACUGGGGCCUCCACACUAAGGAGGGGCAGGGCUGGCAGUGACGAGGGAAACCUCUCGCUGAGGGUUGGGGCAAAGUCACCCCUGGAAAUCGAAGGGGCCGCUGGUGGUCUCUUGAGGUCCACCAGCCUCAAAUGCAUCUCUUCAGACGGUGUUGGGGGCACAACCCUACUCCCCGAAAAGUCGAAAACCCAAUUCAGUUCCUGCGAGUCCCUCUUAGAAUCCAGACCGAGCAUGGGGAGAAAACUGAGCUCUCCGACCACACCCAGGGACAUGCUGUUGUCGCCCACACUGCGUCCUCGGAGGCGGUGUCUGGAGUCCUCUGUGGACGAUGCGGGCUGUCCAGACCUUGGAAAGGAGCCGCUUGUUUUCCAGAACCGCCAGUUUGCCCACCUGAUGGAGGAACCUCUAGGCAGUGACCCAUUCAGCUGGAAACUCCCAAGCCUCGACUACGAACGCAAGACCAAAGUGGACUUCGAUGACUUCCUCCCAGCUAUCCGGAAGCCCCAGACACCUACCUCCUUGGCUGGAUCAGCCAAAGGUGGGCAAGACGGUUCACAGCGUUCAAGCAUCCACUUUGAAACGGAAGAGGCUAACCGUUCCUUUCUCUCGGGGAUCAAGACCAUUUUGAAGAAGAGCCCGGAGCCCAAGGAGGAUCCCGCUCACCUGUCUGACUCGUCCUCAUCCUCCGGCUCCAUCGUGUCCUUCAAAAGUGCUGACAGCAUCAAAAGUCGACCAGGAAUCCCACGACUUGCGGGUGACGGUGGCGAGCGAACGUCCCCCGAGCGGAGAGAGCCAGGGACGGGGAGGAAAGACGACGAUGUUGCGAGCAUAAUGAAGAAAUACCUCCAGAAGUAGGAACCAGUUCAGGAAGUAACAUUUCUGCCAACAACAACAUCCACUCCUACUCAGCUCUUCGUUCCCUGCAAUUCCUGUCUUGCCCGACCCCUGCAGAGUGGAAGAAGGUGAUGGAUGGGCAGAGAAAUGGGAGAUGGACAGCUACCAGGGAAGAAUCUGUGAUUUGGGAGCCUUUUGGUGACAUGCACAUUCAAAGGACUAGGAAAGAAUGGCUUUUUCAAACAGCAUAAAUAGAAAACCAGUGGGCCCGAGCGCUCACUGCUACAUAAUGAACGUGCCUGCCUUUUCCUAACAACAUUUUAAGUCGGUAAUUGGCCCGACAGGGGACGUGAACUGUACACUGAGUCACAGAAUAGUACAGAAAAUCUCAGAAUGGCUUCACCUCCCAUCAGGAAAGCCUCCCGUGUACCAAGCCCUGUAGAGACACAUUUCUGGCAUUUGGAGGAGUGCAGACGUUCAAAAUAAGAAAGAGCUUCAGAGGACAACCGUCCCCUGGGUUCCCGGCCUUUUCCACAUCAGAAGACUCUUUGAUAUGUUCCCCUCUUUCCCUAGGGCCCCUUGUUCUAAAGGAUGCAGCCAGCAAACUAAACUGCUCUGAUCAUCUAAAAAAAAAGGAUAUGUUUCCCACAGAAUAACCACAGAUCUAUAUAACGAAUGAUCACUCAGUUAAUAUGAUGCCUCUAAAAGAUAAGUGGCCUGUCUCAUCUAAAAUAAUCAUAAUAUCAAUAAUAAUAUGAUUUUAUUGGGUGCUUACUAAAGCCCAGAUGAGGGAUUUACAAUGCUUAUCUUACUUAAUCCUUAUGAGACUGUCAUAAAGUUGUCUUUAUUUCACAGUUCAGGAAACAGAGGCACAGAGGAGUUCUGUAACUUACCAAACUAGGUUCAAAACUCAGAUUUAUCUGACUGCAAAGUCACUUUUUUUUUUUUUUUUGGAUUUAGCUUCAAAAGGACAUUGCCUUUACAAAGUUAUUCUUAACCAUGCUACAGUUUUUCUAUUAGUUUUUUUGAAAUAUUGACACUCAUUUGGGGGAAUGCCCAUCAGUUUCUUCACAAGCUUUUGCAAGGUUGGAGGCUUUAGGUUAAGUAUUGUUGUUUUGGUCUCAACUCUUCCCUUAAUAGUUAAGAUAAUGGAGACCCACAGAGGGCUAGAAACUUGCUCAGUAUCAACCUAGUUAAUUAGCAGUAACACUAAUUUUAAAUGCUAGUUUUUAAAAUUCUGGGUCCUGAGCUCUUUAUGUCACACUCAGCUUCAGCAAGUAAUAGUUGAACACCUAUCAGAGGGAGGGCAGAUAAGUAGCAAGCAUGUCAUCACCCUUAUAACCAAAUAGCCAUGGCAGACAUUACUAAUCAAUCAUGGAAAUCUUUCCUGCUGAACCUGGAUGUGGCUCCAUGCAGGCACUCCCAAUCAAUUAGAAUUGGCAAAUGAGAUAAAACUUAUUCACUAUUGACACCAUAUGCAACACUGUUCAAGGUCCUCAAGAUGAUGUAAAACAAGCACAAAAUGAAUGUCUGCUUUCAAAAAUGCUAUCACUUUCAGAAAAUUAUUUCAGUCCAAAGUAAUUUAUUUCAAAGUACUAGGGCAGACCAACUUCUAAUGCCAGUGAUUUUUGGAGACAGGCAAUAUCAUGAAUUGAUAUUGAUAACCUGCUCACAAAAUCAAGAUCAACCAGGAUGAGAGUAGGGAUAGGGACCACCUUGAGGGGACGGGAUAUGAGAAUGUGAGUGGGAGAAGGUGGUUGCUGGAGGGCCAGUCAAUAGGAGAAGGCAUUAACUCAAGAGAAAUGUGUGAGUGCAUGAAGCUGAGGGUGGAGGUGGAAGUGUAAUUUGACAAGGAGGGACACUAAAAUUGAUAGCUGAGAGAGAAUGCGGUAUCCACUGUGCUUCAGGGACUGCAAUAGUUUGAAUGUUUGUCUCCUCAAAUUUCAUGUUGAGUUUGAUCCCCAAAACUGGAGGUGGGGCCCAAUGGGAAGUGUUAGGGUCAAAGAGACAGAUUCCCCAUGAAUGGCUUUGCGCUGUCCUCAUGGUAAUGACUGAGUUCUCACUCAUUACUUCCUGCAAGCGCUGGUUGUUAAAAAGAGCCUAGCAUCUCCCCUGCCUCUCUCUCUUUCUUCCUCUCUCACUGUGGGAUCCCUGCACAUACACUCACCUUUGUCUUCCAUCAUGAGUGGAAGCAGCUUGAGGCCCUCACCAGAUGCAGAUACUGUUUCUUGUACAGCCUGCAGAACCAUGAGUCAAAAAAUCCUCUUUUCUUUAUAAUUACGCAGCCUCAGGAAUUCCUUUAUAGCAACACUAAAUGGACUAAGACAUGGACAAAGCUGAGAUUUAAGGGUGGAAGGAGCAGGUUAAAAGUAUUAAUUUGUUGCAUAUCAACACUUGUGAGUAAGAUAGCUCUUCUCUUUGCCUCUUCACCUUUUUAAAAUAAGUGACCAUGAUAAAAGAAAAGGUUAUAGAAUUGGGAGAAAAGGACAAUAUAAUAUAGGCCCUCCCAAAACCUUUGGGACUGUUUCCCACUAUGAGGUAGACUUGGACAAGGACAUUUUCUGACUCCCAGAAGUGGUGAAUGCCACGUGGUCAGCAAAUUCUGUCAAGACUCUUCCAGCCAAACAAGUCUAUGUCAUCUUGCUUGUUACUUUACCUCUUCAAAGGCAAUGGCUACUGGGAUGAUGGAUCUUGGAAGCAUUAGCAAAUGGAGUCAAAAGAACUAAAGGAAGAGGACCCAAAUGUGGAGUGAAUGAGACGGAGAUUGUGUGAGUUAUUAAGUAUAGAACAGCCCAACUCCAGGGUGGGAAAAGAGGAAUUAUGCAAAUGCCAGGAUAAGCAUUUCCACUUUGGAAUUCUAAGAAAUGAGAGUUUUCUAGAGAAGUUGUUCAUCAAGGGAGAAAUUCUAUGUCAGGAAUGUGUCAAAAUUUAGAACCAAGCCCCUUUCAUAGGCAAGGGAAGCUCAGGUGCCCAUUGAGGAUGCCCUGAGUUUGGGAAAGAGGACGGUGUCUUCCUGGGCUAAGCAGCUGUCUGCACCACUUUGGAUCAAUUUCCACUUGAACAUGUUGCCACUGCCUCCCAAACUCCAUCUUCUAACCCCAAGAAUGCAUUGUAUAGAAUUAGUCUCACAAUUCCACAGACAGAAUUAGCCUCUGCAAUGAGAGAUCAGCCCUUGACUUGUGGUUAAUUACGUACAAUUCAAAAUCAACCCCCUGUUGUUCACAUUUCCCUUGUGCCUGGAGCUCUUGGAAGAAGAAAUUGCAUGCUGUCCUGGGAAAGGCUGGAGAAGGUGUAUGGCACUAGGUUGCAACGUGUUGGCAUGUCCUAAAGACACAUGUGAGAAUAAUGUGGUCGAUUAUUGUGACAGCUGAGGACAGACUUUGCUAGUCAGAAUUCUGGGGAAACAACUUUAAGCAUAAAAAUGUUUCUUUUAAAUGAUUAUUUUAUUAGCCUUGUGAUCAGUGCAGUACAGGAUUCUGUUCCUGUUGAAAGAAGUAAAGCAUUCGUACAUCCCCAGCGUCCUUUAGUGAGCUCUCUAGGGCAGGGACCAGGGAACUAUGGCCUGUGGGCCACAUUCUACUCACUCCUUGUUUUUAUAUAGUUUCAUCAGAACAUAUAAUUUGUUUACAUAUGGUCUAUGGCUGCUUUGAACUACAACAGAAGAUUUGAGUAGCUGCAGCAGAGACCAAAUACCCUGAAUGGCUCACAGAGCCUAAAGUAUGUACUACCUGGCUCUUUAUAGGAAAAAGUUCACCAACCCCUGAUUUAAGGAAAUAUCAGAGAAACCACCUAACCUUGUGUUUUGAAGCUGGAUUCUGCUGGUCCAUGACCUCCUGACCUUUUCCCUGCUCUGUUCUGCAAUGCAGGAAGUUGCAAAGGAGCUGUCUCCCACAGGUGUGUUUGAGGCUCCUGGGUCAACUGGCUUCUGUCUGGAUUCAGCAAUGGCAGAUACUGACAGUAGACUAAAGAGGGAGAAGAUUAAACACACACAUACACACGUAUACACACACAGAUAUGUAUACACACAUACACAUAUACACAAAUAUACAUAUACACACAUCCACACAUUUAUACAUACGCACACAUGCACACUACACACAUAUGUACAUACAUACACACAUGCACACAUACAUAUACACAUGCACACAUAUAUACAUAUACACAUAUACAUACAAACAUGCAUACAUUUAUACAUAUACACAUAUGCACAUAUAUGCACAUAAACACAUGCAUACAUAUAUACAUAUACACAAUAUACACAUAUACAUAUAUACACAAACACACAGUUUUACAUAUACACAUAUACACACAUAUACACAAACAUACAUAUACACACAUACAUUCACACAUACACAUGCACACACCACAUAUGCACACAUGAACACACAUAUACACACAUACCACAUAUGCACACACAUACACACACACACACACACACAAUUCAGUCAGCAUCUCCAGUGGCAACUGUGAACCUUCUGUAGCCCCAGCUACUGUUGGCUUGGCCCCCUGUAGUGCCAGCUUCUGCUGAGGAGCCCCAGACCCUGGACUCCAGUAACACUGUCCUUUGACCCUCCAGCCAGGAGGUGGUAGGAGCUUCCUGCUGUACUGUUCUCUGUGAUAUCCCAUGGUUGUUAGUAAAUUCCUCAGCCCUUCCAUCCCCUGUAUAACCAGUUUCUUUUAUCAAAUUCCUGAUUUUAAAUCCAUAGAUUUGUUUCUGUUUUGUUGGUUGGAUCCUGACAGGUCCAGGUCCUGACCCUGAAUCCUGGCCAUAGCACCAAAGUCCUGUUAGGGUCUGCUUUCUGUUUUCCACCUUGAUGGGGCUGUUGGAGUUUUGCUUUGAAUACUGGGUGGCUGUGUUCUUCCAAAUUGUUGGAGCAGACAGCUUCAUUAGCUAAGGAGUCCUUGCUACAAUCAUGGGCUUCUCUAGCCUCACCAGAUGAAUAUCCAUCUCCAUCCUCAAAUAUCUCUCUGCUGCUCACAGUGAGAUGGGACCCCAGGGAGGUGGCACUAUCAUAGCUCUCAGUUCCUGUGUCCCUAUUGCCGAGAAACGUCAUCUACCACCAAGAAAGGUCAUCUACCACCGAGAAAGGUCAUCUACCACCGAGAAAGGUCAUUCUUCUGAUGCUCUUUGCUUGUUUCCACAGUGCUCACACUCCCAACACACCUCUGCCCAACUCCAGCCUAGAAUAAUAACUCCAACCUCACUCCUACCACAGAUUGUUUGGCUUUGAUGCUGUCAACAUUUGAAUCUUGGCCCUUCCUAGCCCAUCAUUUUUCCAUGAUUUAAAAAUUGAUGCUGAAAAACAAAAAAAAUCAGUGGUCAGAACAUUUAAGAAAAUACUGGAUUAAACAAAUUAAAAGAGGUCUCUUCAAUACAGGACUUCUCAGAGCCUUUAAAAUAAGAGGCAAUUGAGACAGCAGUGUUUUCAAAACUAAUUUGAGCAUGGAACUUUUCUUCUCUGUGUGGGGAUCAUCUCAUGGGGCUUAGGAUCCAUGAAACAUUAUUUGAUAUGAUGAAUAUUUGUUGUUUCUGUCUGUCCAGAUUCCAUCUUUCUCUUACCCCCUUCUUCUGGUGACAGUAUAACUCUCUUGAGUCAGAGACCUUUUCCAUCUGGUAUGGGUGGGACUGACCUUCCUGCCAUCAUCUUCAACAACAGAGUUGUGAUGUCAUCCAGUUGUGUCCCCAGUGAUUGAGGAUGGGAAGGUAUCUAAAUUGGGACAACCAGAGUCCUUAGGGAGACUUUUCUAACAAGGAUUUCAGGGAGAACUUGUUCUUUCUUUCACUGGGGGUAUUGAGUUGCUAGAAUAAUAGUGGGCCAGGGGUCUAAUGGCUAUCAGGUAUGAAGAAGCUAUUGGAAUAGAAACCAAGCCAAGAGCCAUAACAGAAUUGACAGCUAGAGAGAAAGCAGAACCCUGGCAAUAUUUCCUGAGCCCCUGGACCCAGUCAAGUCGGAAACUGGUUCCAUUCCUUUGACUCCCUAGUUACAUGAGCUAAUAAAUCCUACCAUUCCAUUUUUAUUUUACUAUUAUUAAUAAUUUUAUUUUUGCUUAAGGUAGGUUGAGUUCACCCUUUUGUCUCUCACAAAUAAAAUAUGCCUGGCUAAUAGAUGGAGAAAACACAGCCUCUUCUGGCUCAAAGUACAUGCCAUGCUGCCUUGGGUCAGAAUCCCCCUGCUGGCUUUGAAUCCUUAGAAUGCAAUCCCCAAGGCCAAGCCCUGUGCUUGGUAUUCUGUCCCAACCACUCAAGGUCCCCUGAAGAGAAAAGGCCAUGUAGAAAUCAGGGCUUGAACGGGAGAAGACAGAUGGAGCAGGACAGGAACACAGGGUAGCCUCCAUCCAUAAUUCAUCUUUCCAAAGCCAGGUCGCAGUCUCAACAUCCUGGAUCUUGGUUUUGUGUGAACCCAUGAGAUGGGGCCUUCAGGGAAUGGACACCCAGCACUGUGCCUCUUCUUAAAUUAUGCCAUGAUUCUACAUGUGCCCUAAAUUUCCAUCUUCUCUGCUGUUACACCGUUCCAACACCAAAGAUCAUUGAUUCCAGCCCUGGAAUGAUUUACUUGGUGCAACUAGAAAACAACAUAUGUUGACUUGAAUGAUAUUCAGAUUAAUAAAUGAGAGACUCCAAGGCCUUCCAGCUGAGAAGCAGUUUUCAUUCAGAAAUUACUCAUGUGGAAUGGCAGAAGUGCCAAGAAUACAGGUGUAAACAAGUGGCAGAAAUGAGAAGAACCCGAUGCGUGAAGAGAACAAUGAAAAUAUUACCUCGUAUGCUGAACGCCCCUCAACAUUGGAAAAGAGCUUCCACAAACAAUCUUGGUGAUGCUCAAACCACCCUCUCAACAGGUGAAGGUGAUUAGCCCCAUUCUUCAGAGGAGAUCAUCCAGGUGGCCAAGAAUACAAAAUGACCCAAAGUGCCCCAUAUCAGGUAGCCAGAGGGGGCAGUCAGGGCUUGAAUGUGAGAUGCCUGACUCAGGUCCAGGUCUCUUUGCACAUCAGACAGGGAUGGUUAGCUGGUUUCCAUCUCUGAUCAACAUGGAGCUGACUCUAUUUCCCAUUUUUCAGCCAUCCCAACAACUCCACCCCAAAAUCCAAAGUUUGCCCCUCAACACUAAACACCACUUUGCUGGAAUGUCUAUGUUUUCCUUCGACCAUUAGGCUUCCCAGUUGUCACCUGGGGAAACUGUGACUAUAGAUUCCAGCUCAAACCAUAAAGGGUUAAGAACUAAAAAUAGUGUGAUAGCAAUUAAAGCUCUUCUUUUUCCUAA